GCCUCAACCUGACACUCAGCAGCAAGUUAGGCCUAUCUACAAAUCUCCUGCUCUGUGCCCGCGCAGUCCAGUGGAGGAGAUAUUCCUAAUUAGGGGGCACUUCCAAGGGGCGGAGUCUCCGCGGCGAGUGGCCGUGGAGGGGCGCAAGGCAGACGGUCUCCAGCCACGAUACCUGGGCCAAUCCCAGCCUGUCACGUCAUGCCUAGUGAGCUGAACAAGCUGCGUAACUGUCGUGUGCCUCAGUUUCCCCACGUGUAUAAUGGAAAUGAUUACAAUAAACAGGACCUUUUUGAGGAGUUGCCAUGAGGACUGUCAGGCCGGCCAGCUCCAGCAGGUCAGUCUGCGAGUCAGGAGAAAUCACUGGGAAAUCCCCUGGAUAUAGUAACACAUGACAGCACCAUUGAAUUAAUCAUCAACUUUGUAACGUGAUCUCUGGCCCAUAAAAAGCAGACCUGCUGAAUCUUUGGUAACCUGUCCACUGGCCUUCUCCAGGCAGUUCCUUCUAGACCUGGGGACCUGUGCCCGAGGACCUUAGACUGAUGGGUGCCCAGCUCUGCUUCGAGGCCAACGCCAAGGCGCCCCGAGAGGCACUUCGCUUCCAUGCCGAGGCCAAGGGCGCACAGGUGCGUCUGGACACGCGUGGCUGCAUCGCGCACAGGCGCACCACGUUCCACGACGGCAUCGUGUUCAGCCAGCGGCCGGUGCGCCUGGGCGAGCGUGUGGCGCUGCGAGUGCUGCGGGAGGAGAGCGGCUGGUGCGGCGGCCUCCGCGUGGGCUUCACGCGCCUGGACCCCGCGUGCGUGUCCGUGCCCAGCCUGCCGCCCUUCCUGUGCCCCGACCUGGAGGAGCAGAGCCCGACGUGGGCGGCCGUGCUGCCUGAGGGCUGCGCGCUCACUGGGGACUUGGUCCGCUUCUGGGUGGACCGCCGCGGCUGCCUCUUCGCCAAGGUCAACGCCGGCUGCCGGCUCCUGCUGCGUGAGGGCGUGCCCGUCGGCGCCCCGCUCUGGGCCGUGAUGGACGUGUAUGGGACCACUAAGGCCAUCGAGCUGCUGGAUCCCACAGCCAGCCGGCUCCCAACACCCAUGCCAUGGGACCUCAGCAACAAGGCUGUGCCUGAGCCCAAAGCCACACCAGGAGAGGAGUGUGCCAUCUGCUUCUAUCACGCUGCCAACACCCGCCUUGUGCCCUGCGGCCACACAUACUUCUGCAGAUACUGUGCCUGGCGGGUCUUCAGCGAUACGGCCAAGUGCCCUGUGUGCCGCUGGCAGAUAGAGGCGGUAGCCCCUGCGCAGGGCCCUCCUGCUCUGAGGGUUGAGGAAGGCUCAUGAAAGGAGGCUUCCCAGUAUGAGUGGCAGCCCGGGCCUAGAUCUGAGUCUGGCCCCUGCAGAGAGGAAGGAGGCGCAGCCCUACCUUCUUUCUGGGGAAGAGUCAGAAAGGCUGAUUAGCAAGAGGUGCGGCAGAGAGAGGAAGGCAGGGAGGUGCUGUCUGCUGCCUCCACCUGUUCCCCAACAGGAUAGCAAGGAAAAACCCCUCUUUCUGUCCAUGCCAGAACUAUCCUUCUGAUGGGGUGCUUUGUUUAGAGAUGGGGUGGCCCAAUCCCCAAUCAGUUUUACAUCUGAGGGAGUUCAGGUAUCUGUUGUGACUGGUGAAGCCCUGUACCUCCUGGGUAUUGAAGAACCUGGACUUGAAGCAGGAGGUAUCUGCAAGGAAUGUAUAAAGUUCCACAUGGAAGCUGGGUUGCCUCCCACAAGUCCCCAGUAGAGUGGAUCUGUAGUUACCCGCCCUGCCUCCCUUUCAGGGUGGUCAUGAGGUCCCAGAGAGACCAUGCAUCUGAAGAUGAUUUAAAACAUGAAAGUGUAUUGUUGUCACUGUGGUAAUUUCCUUGCCAGUUUCUGAGAUAUCAAAAUAAAGUUUGUGUUUCCUGAA